UUUUUUUAAUUUUUUUAUUUUUUUUUUUAGAGAUGGAGUUUCACUUUUGUUGCCCAGGCUGGAGUGCAAUGGCCUGAUCUCAGCUCACUGCAACCUCCGCCUCCCAGGUUCAGGCUAUUCUUCUGCCUCAGCCUCCCGAGUGGCUGGGAUUACAGGCACCUGCCACCAUGCCCAGAUAAUUUUUGUAUUUUUAGUAGAGAAAGGUUUUGCCAUGUUGGCCAGGCUGGUCUUGAACUCCUGACCUCAGGUGAUCCACCCACCUCAGCCUCCCAAAGUGUUGGGAUUACAGGCAUGAGCCACCGCGCCCAGCCCCUAUGAUUCUUAUGAGGACAAAUUGCCUAUUUUAAAAAUGUCUAGAUCAGUAUCAUGCAUAUAAGUUCAUUGUGUGUACAUUAAAUUAAAUAAAAACAUGUCUGUAAACCCCUUUUAAAAGCUAUAAGGAACAACAGGAGGUAAAUUUUUCUUAACUCAGUAUGUUAUUUACUAAUAUUGUAUCAUUAACAUCAUCAUUACACUAUUUUGUCAAAAGAUUUGAAAAAAAGUGAGUUUGAUAAAUGUUUUAAAGUUAGAAUUCAUUACAGACAAAUAAGUGAUUCAAAUUUUUGAAUGACAGUGAAUGAAUAUUUUUAAAACUUUGUUCUAGGGGCUGUAGUUGUAAUUGUGUUUCAGUUGUAAAUGUCUCAUUAACUUUAUAAAUUGAUUCCUGUUAUUUGUUUGGAAGUGAAAGCACAAUAAUAUCAAAUUCAGCUAAUAGCUCGCUUUGUCAGAUCACUGUAUUUUAGAUCGUUUCUGAUUUCGUUUGUCUCAAAUUAGAUGAACUUUUUUUUUUUUUUAAGUCCCGGUAGCUUGAUUCAAAAUGUGACAUUUUGGCACUCAGUAGUUAAUGAUACUAUUCUAAACUUUAAAAUCAAAAAGGAAAUAUAUUUACAUCUAAAUGACCAUACUGUCUUCUGCUCAUCAUGUCUGCUAUUUAAUUUUUAUUUUUAGUGACCUCAGAGUAGGAAUACCUUACAUAGGCUCAUGUCUGAAAAUGAUUUGAAAAGCCAGGUAAACUUGCCUUUUCUGGAUGCUUUUUUCUCCUCUGAGUGAGGUGAGGACACUGAGGUUAAGGUGUGUCAUGCAUGUAUUUUUUUACUUAUUUUCAGUCUAAGCCAGUUAUAUGAGUAGCUCUAAUGGUUAACUUUGUAAAUCAUUCAGGAAUCUGGCUGCUUUCUGAAAACAUACCUGGGCCUUCAGGCAGCCAUCUACAGGUGAUUGCGCCUGGAUGUUUGCCUAAAGAUGAUUUAGAAAAUUGGUUGGAAGCUUUGCUCUUCCCCAGCUAUCAAGAAUUAACCUGCCAGAAAUUUGCAAACACAGCAAAGUUAUGUUAAUGAUUCUGACUCAUGCACAAGAUUUUCUUUUUUAAAAAAUAUAAAGCUGACUAUUCCAAAUUCCAAAGAUUCAGCAUUUAUUAUUUGGUAAUUUACUUUUGUAUUGCAGAAUGAGUAGGACAUUCAUUACCAGACCCCUUGACUGUCUCAAACCUUUAGGUUGUUGACUCAGUGUGCUUAUUGGAGUUAGAGGAGUUCAUUUACAUUCAGCAUCUUUGGGUUAAGUCAAGGUGAAAAAGCAUUCACCGUACAGUCCCCAAUUCACUUCCAUCUUCUAGAAUUGUGAGUCAUUUUUUUAGAAGUUUUAAAAUGGGGAUUGUAAACUCAGAAGCCUCAUGGGUCAGGUAGGUGUCAUUAAUGAGUUAGGGAUAUAGUGUGUAAAUGUUGCCAGAACCUCACAUUAUUUUUUAAGAAACUAUUAGUCCAGAUUUUUCUUAUGAAAGUUUCUACCUUCUUAGUGCUAUUUGAAAUUAUUUUAAAAUCUUGAAUGCUAAAGAGAUAAAUAAAUAAGAAUGACAUGACUGUGCAUGACCAGGUCUCUUCAUUCUUUAACUUCUACCUGAAAACCAGGCAUACUCUUCAACAUCAUGCUGCUAGAUAUUCUGUUGUGAAUCACUUACCCUUAUAGAUCCCUCCUCUUGGGGAUUUCCACUUACUCCCUCACUGCACGGUUGUACAAGUGUGAACAUGCCUGGAAACUAUAAUUAUCUGUGGAUUUUGACAAAAGAUCCUCAGUAGUUGUUACCAUGCUUAUUAAGUUCCCGAACAAAUUUUUAUCUCCUAAAUUAACAUCAGGUUGACAGGCAUCCAGGAUGGAUGCUGAUUCUCUGGUUAUCUGCACACUCGAAACUUAGUUUUAUCAGUCAUUUUUCUUCCUUGUGGAUCACCUCAGAACCUUUUACAUUUUUUCCAGUUUAUUUUUUGUCUUUCAGUAUCAUCCCUGCUGUUGACCCAGUGCACACCACAGCACCAAUGGCUUCCUUCAUUCUUAUGUCUUUUAAUUUUUUUUCAAGUAAUUUCAUAAUAUGACACUCUUGUACUUUUUUCAUCACUGAAAGAAUAGGAUGGAUAAUGUACACAAACUAACUCAAAUUGCAGCAUAAAUAUCAUGAACAUACAUUAGAUUAAAAGAUGUUGCUAUGGCUGACAUUAGAAUGACAUCUCCUGACUGCUAAAUUCAUUUGUUGCUGACAGUCAGGGUUGGUUGAUAUCCCGUUGUUCUUGAACACAGACUUGCUCACUUCAGUGAAAAUUUUAAGGCAGAAAGUUCUCAAGAGCUGCUGUCUGAAGCAAAUCUUAUGGCCAGAAGUUAUAGUAUAUUCAGACUGAUGCGCUAGAGUUUUCGAAAUGAUUCAUUUGGUCUUCUUAUGAAAUAGUUUUGAGAUUCUUCUUAGUAAACAUUGGCUUGAUUUUGUUUCUGUAAAAUUUUUUUUUCUUCUCCGCUGUAUGGAGAAGACUGUCAUGAGUGAACUUGGCAAUUGCCUUGUUAAAACCAGUUGGACGUUAUCUUCCACAUUGCGAAGCUAUACAUGUCUGAUAUGUUCUGAAAGAAUAGAAUUUAUAGUUAGAUAUACUAUUUUUGAUUAUUUACUCAGAAGGAGACAUGUAAUUAUUCUUAUGUUGUCAUGAAAAUCUAUUAAAUGCAUUUAUAUUUCACAUCAAUGUUACGAAAUUCCAUUAUUAUUAUUUUACAGAGGGGAAGCCAAGAUACAGGAGUGGAAAUUACUUGGCCACAUCGCACAGAAAUGUUUAAUUUGGUAAAUUGGAGGAAAAAAACAUGGAUUUUUAGCAAUUGAAGAGCAAAUUAAGGUUUCAGAUUUGGGAUAUUGGUGUUUCUGUUUUGGAGAAAUUAUUCUUUUUCUUUUUAAUUUGAAGAAAAAUCAUCAGUCUUGGAAUACAGAAGAGAAACUAGAAAUAUACGUAUUUUGUUUCACAUUUGAACAGUCAUUCUUGAGGAAUACUCCAUACCUGAGUAGACAGCCAUGUGGCCAUCGCAGCUACUAAUUUUCAUGAUGCUCUUAGCUCCAAUAAUUCAUGGUGGCAAGCACAGUGAACGACAUCCUGCCCUUGCUGCUCCAUUGCGACACGCUGAGCGCAGCCCAGGAGGCGCUCUUCCACCCAGACAUCUGCUUCAGCAGCCAGCUGCAGAGCGCACCGCUGCUCAUCGUGGACAAGGGCCCCGUGGAGCUACCAGAGGAGUUCGCGGUCCAGGUGCCCAAGGAGCACAGAUUGCAGCGCAAGCUUUCAGCCGUGCCCCAAUUCCAAUGGCUGUGGUCCGCAGAGAGCUAUCCUGUGAGAGCUAUCCUAUAGAGCUUCGCUGUCCAGGAACAGACGUCAUCAUGAUAGAAAGUGCCAACUAUGGCAGGACUGAUGACAAAAUUUGUGACUCUGACCCUGCUCAGAUGGAGAAUAUCCGAUGUUAUCUGCCAGAUGCCUAUAAGAUUAUGUCUCAAAGAUGCAAUAACAGAACCCAGUGUGCAGUGGUGGCAGGUCCUGAUGUUUUUCCAGACCCGUGUCCAGGAACCUAUAAAUACCUUGAAGUGCAGUAUGAAUGUGUCCCUUACAAAGUGGAACAAAAAGUUUUUCUUUGUCCUGGACUACUAAAAGGAGUAUACCAGAGUGAACAUUUGUUUGAGUCCGACCACCAAUCUGGGGCGUGGUGCAAAGACCCUCUGCAGGCAUCUGACAAGAUUUAUUAUAUGCCCUGGACUCCCUACAGAACUGAUACCCUGACUGAGUAUUCAUCCAAGGAUGACUUCAUUGCUGGAAGACCAACUACAACCUACAAGCUCCCUCACAGGGUGGAUGGCACAGGAUUUGUAGUGUAUGAUGGAGCUUUGUUCUUCAACAAAGAGCGCACCAGGAACAUAGUAAAGUUUGAUUUGCGGACUAGGAUAAAGAGUGGAGAGGCUAUCAUAGCAAAUGCCAAUUACCAUGAUACCUCCCCUUACCGAUGGGGAGGCAAAUCUGACAUAGACCUGGCAGUAGAUGAGAAUGGGCUAUGGGUAAUCUAUGCAACAGAACAAAACAAUGGUAAAAUUGUCAUUAGUCAAUUGAACCCUUACACCCUACGGAUCGAAGGAACAUGGGAUACUGCAUAUGAUAAAAGGUCAGCUUCCAAUGCCUUUAUGAUUUGUGGAAUUCUGUAUGUGGUCAAAUCUGUAUAUGAGGAUGAUGACAAUGAGGCUACUGGAAAUAAGAUUGACUACAUUUACAACACUGACCAAAGCAAGGAUAGUUUGGUGGAUGUACCCUUUCCUAAUUCAUACCAGUACAUUGCAGCUGUGGAUUACAACCCCAGGGACAACCUACUUUAUGUAUGGAAUAACUAUCACGUCGUGAAAUAUUCUUUGGAUUUUGGACCUCUGGAUAGUAGAUCAGGGCAGGCACAUCAUGGACAAGUUUCAUACAUUUCUCCGCCAAUUCACCUUGACUCUGAGCUAGAAAGACCCUCUGUUAAAGAUAUCUCUACCACAGGACCUCUUGGCAUGGGAAGCACUACCACCAGUACCACCCUUCGGACCACAACUUUGAGCCCAGGAAGGAGUACCACCCCGUCAGUGUCAGGAAGAAGAAACCGGAGUACUAGUACCCCAUCUCCAGCUGUCGAGGUACUUGAUGACAUGACCACACACCUUCCAUCAGCAUCGUCCCAAAUCCCAGCUCUCGAAGAGAGCUGUGAGGCUGUGGAAGCCCGAGAAAUCAUGUGGUUUAAGACUCGUCAAGGACAGAUAGCAAAGCAGCCAUGCCCUGCAGGAACUAUAGGUGUAUCAACUUAUCUAUGCCUUGCUCCUGAUGGAAUUUGGGAUCCCCAAGGUCCAGAUCUCAGCAACUGUUCUUCUCCUUGGGUCAAUCAUAUAACACAGAAGUUGAAAUCUGGUGAAACAGCUGCCAACAUUGCUAGAGAGCUGGCUGAACAGACAAGAAAUCACUUGAAUGCUGGGGACAUCACCUACUCUGUCCGGGCCAUGGACCAGCUGGUAGGCCUCCUAGAUGUACAGCUUCGGAACUUGACCCCAGGUGGAAAAGAUAGUGCUGCCCGGAGUUUGAACAAGCUUCAGAAAAGAGAGCGCUCUUGCAGAGCCUAUGUCCAGGCAAUGGUCGAGACAGUUAACAACCUCCUUCAGCCACAAGCUUUGAAUGCAUGGAGAGACCUGACUACGAGUGAUCAGCUGCGUGCGGCCACCAUGUUGCUUCAUACUGUGGAGGAAAGUGCUUUUGUGCUGGCUGAUAACCUUUUGAAGACUGACAUUGUCAGGGAGAAUACAGACAAUAUUAAAUUGGAAGUUGCAAGACUGAGCACAGAAGGAAACUUAGAAGACCUAAAAUUUCCAGAAAACAUGGGCCAUGGAAGCACUAUCCAGCUGUCUGCAAAUACCUUAAAGCAAAAUGGCCGAAAUGGAGAGAUCAGAGUGGCCUUUGUCCUGUAUAACAACUUGGGUCCUUAUUUAUCCACGGAGAAUGCCAGUAUGAAGUUGGGAACGGAAGCUUUGUCCACAAAUCAUUCUGUUAUUGUCAAUUCCCCUGUUAUUACGGCAGCAAUAAACAAAGAGUUCAGUAACAAGGUUUAUUUGGCUGAUCCUGUGGUAUUUACUGUUAAACAUAUCAAGCAGUCAGAGGAAAAUUUCAACCCUAACUGUUCAUUUUGGAGCUACUCCAAGCGUACAAUGACAGGUUAUUGGUCAACACAAGGCUGUCGGCUCCUGACAACAAAUAAGACACAUACUACAUGCUCUUGUAACCACCUAACAAAUUUUGCAGUACUGAUGGCACAUGUGGAAGUUAAGCACAGUGAUGCGGUCCAUGACCUCCUUCUGGAUGUGAUCACGUGGGUUGGAAUUUUGCUGUCCCUUGUUUGUCUCCUGAUUUGCAUCUUCACAUUUUGCUUUUUCCGGGGGCUCCAGAGUGACCGUAACACCAUCCACAAGAACCUCUGCAUCAGUCUCUUUGUAGCAGAGCUGCUCUUCCUGAUUGGGAUCAACCGAACUGACCAACCAAUUGCCUGUGCUGUUUUCGCUGCCCUGUUACAUUUCUUCUUCUUGGCUGCCUUCACCUGGAUGUUCCUGGAGGGGGUGCAGCUUUAUAUCAUGCUGGUGGAGGUUUUUGAGAGUGAACAUUCACGUAGGAAAUACUUUUAUCUGGUCGGCUAUGGGAUGCCUGCACUCAUUGUGGCUGUGUCAGCUGCAGUAGACUACAGGAGUUAUGGAACAGAUAAAGUAUGUUGGCUCCGACUUGACACCUACUUCAUUUGGAGUUUUAUAGGACCAGCAACUUUGAUAAUUAUGCUUAAUGUAAUCUUCCUUGGGAUUGCUUUAUAUAAAAUGUUUCAUCAUACUGCUAUACUGAAACCUGAAUCAGGCUGUCUUGAUAACAUCAACUAUGAGGAUAACAGACCCUUCAUCAAGUCAUGGGUUAUAGGUGCAAUAGCUCUUCUCUGCCUAUUAGGAUUGACCUGGGCCUUUGGACUCAUGUAUAUUAAUGAAAGCACAGUCAUCAUGGCCUAUCUCUUCACCAUUUUCAAUUCUCUACAGGGAAUGUUUAUAUUUAUUUUCCAUUGUGUCCUACAGAAGAAGGUACGAAAAGAGUAUGGGAAAUGCCUGCGAACACAUUGCUGUAGUGGCAAAAGUACAGAGAGUUCCAUUGGUUCAGGGAAAACAUCUGGUUCUCGAACUCCUGGACGCUACUCCACAGGCUCACAGAGCCGAAUCCGUAGAAUGUGGAAUGACACGGUUCGAAAGCAGUCAGAGUCUUCCUUUAUUACUGGAGACAUAAACAGUUCAGCGUCACUCAACAGAGGAGCCAUGGCUAAUCAUCUUAUAAGCAAUGCUCUGCUUCGUCCGCAUGGUACUAACAAUCCCUAUAAUACAUUGCUUGGGGAACCGGCGGUCUGUAACAACCCUUCUGUCAGCAUGUACAACGCACAAGAGCCCUACAGAGAGACAAAGGGGCUUCUGAACAAUGCCAGGGAUACAAGUGUCAUGGAUACUCUACCACUGAAUGGUAACCAUGGCAAUAGUUACAGCAUUGCCAGCGGCGAAUACCUGAGCAACUGUGUGCAAAUCAUAGACCGUGGCUAUAACCAUAACGAGACCGCCCUAGAGAAAAAGAUUCUGAAGGAACUCACUUCCAACUAUAUCCCUUCUUACCUGAACAACCAUGAGCGCUCCAGUGAACAGAACAGGAAUCUGAUGAACAAGCUGGUGAAUAACCUUGGCAGUGGAAGGGAAGAUGAUGCCAUUGUCCUGGAUGAUGCCACCUCGUUUAACCACGAGGAGAGUUUGGGCCUGGAACUCAUUCAUGAGGAAUCUGAUGCUCCUUUGCUGCCCCCAAGAGUAUACUCCACCGAGAACCACCAGCCACACCAUUAUACCAGAAGGCGGAUCCCCCAAGACCACAGUGAGAGCUUUUUCCCUUUGCUAACCAACGAGCACACAGAAGAUCUCCAGUCACCCCAUAGAGACUCUCUCUAUACCAGCAUGCCGACACUGGCUGGUGUGGCCGCCACAGAGAGUGUUACCACCAGCACCCAGACCGAACCCCCACCGGCCAAAUGUGGUGAUGCCGAAGAUGUUUACUACAAAAGCAUGCCAAACCUAGGCUCCAGAAACCACGUCCAUCAGCUGCAUACUUACUACCAGCUAGGUCGCGGCAGCAGUGAUGGAUUUAUAGUUCCUCCAAACAAAGAUGGGACCCCUCCCGAGGGAAGUUCAAAAGGACCGGCUCAUUUGGUCACUAGUCUAUAGAAGAUGACACAGAAAUUGGAACCAACAAAACUGCUAACACCUUGUUGACUGUUCUGAGUUGAUAUAAGCAGUGGUAAUAAUGUGUGUACUCCUAAAUCUUUAUGCUGUCCUCUAAAGACAAACACAAACUCUCAGACUUUUUUUUUUUUAAUGGGAUUUUUAGGUCAGCCCAGGGGAGAAAGAUAACUGCUAAAAUUCCCCUGUACCCCAUCCUUUCUUGUCCUUUCCCCUUCAGAUGGAGACUUCAUUAUGUUAAUGAACAAGAUAUGAAGAAAAUGGCACUCAUUGUGGCCUUGUUGAAUUAUGUUGUGUAUGUUUUAACAUCUCUGAUGCUGUGUUACUAAAAUUACAAGGACCUGCUUUUUAAAAGGCCAGAACAAUUGUCUGAAAUUAGUAACAAUGCUGCAUCUAGAUUGGAGUGCUGCACAAACAAACAUAAGAGCAAAGCAAAACUGUAUCACAUAGGGUUUUUGGUCACUCACAACCUGAAUUCACCACAGCUGGAAUAGCUGUGGAAAACAAAAUAAAACAACAAAAUUAAUAAUGAAAUGGAGGGGAAUUCUAGAAUUAUAUGCUAAAUGCAUAUUUUAUGAUUUGCUGUAUUAACUGAUGAUAAAACUAAUGGCAGAAAAAGAAGUUGAGCAAUUUCUAUGUAAUGUACAGAUACUAGCAUUGCACAUAUAGUCUGCUUUCUGUUCCUCCAGAAUUUGAGUCCUGUUAAUGUAGUAGAAAAAAAAAAAAGAAAUUUUCUUUUUCUUUUGUGCUGGUCUUGCAAGUUUGUCUACCAGUAAGAGAGCAAAGUUUCCUUCCUUUCUUCUCUUUCUUCAUUUUCUUUUUUUCUUUUUUGCCUUUUAUUCCUUUAAAAUUUCGCCUGGCAAAAAAUAAAUAAAUGGAACUAUCACUUUAUAAGAAUCAUUUUCUAGUAAUGCAAACAAAUUAUUUUUUACAAAAAAACAAAAUAAAUAAAAUUAGACUUCCUUCCCUCACUAUAUAUCUUUAUGCAGUCAGAAUAUUUCCAACAGUGUUUUUUGCAAAUUAGAGCAGGACAAACUUUUAUGUUUACAGGGCACGUCUGUUGUAAUGCAAAGCAUAUUUGGCAAGCAGUUCAUCACCAGGACACUAGCUAUGAUUCUAGAAGUCAAAAGGUGUCUAUAGAACUAGUGGGGCUUCUGCAUGUGAAAAACGGUUUUCCAUAGGCAUUAAAGUGCUGAAUGCUCAGUCUGAUCAACAAGUGGGCACCUGCACUACCACUUUUUAGAGGAAAUUCACUCCCUCGUAAGCAUUGGAAGGUCAAAUUAUUUUGAAGUGAUUUUUUUAAAAAAAAGUCUUCUGUUUAUUAACAGGAAAAUUUAUUUAUUUGACAGGAUUUUGAGUAAUGUAGGAAUACAAAAGGUAAAUUAGCAGCACAUAUAAUUUUUUUUUAAUUUAUGAUCCAUUUUGUAUGGUCUCAAAGUUGGAUGACCUCAUUACUAAUAUUUGUUGUAAAAGUGAAACUUGUUUGCCAACCAAUAAACAACUGAUUGAGAUUUAGAAGAUAUUGUAUUGAUGUAUGUACUAUAUGAUUAAUCAGUCUUUUUAUUUUUCUCGCCUUUCUUUCUUUCUGUUUUCAAUACAUAAACUUUGCUAAUCCUCUGUGGCCCAAAUGAGCCAUGCAAAAGAAAUCAAUCUGCCUAGAUGAAUAAGCUAAGCACAAAAUCAUACAGGUUUGCAGACAAAGUAAACCAGAAAAAUGGAAUGGGCAUGUUUAUUUUGGAUGAAAUCAGAUGCAUAACUUAAUGUUGAGCAGGUUAACAUAUAUGUUACUAUUUGCUUAUCUAUAAACCAGCUGCAGUCACUAUGCUUACCUUUAAAACCAGAUUCAAUCAGAGAUAUAAAUAUGAAAUUUGGGGGCUGGGUGAGUCAUAUUUUUUCCUCCUUUGUACAUUGCAUUUUGAUGUUAGAAAUUCAAAUUCCCUCAAUUUGCUAAAAGCUGCAAAGAGAAUAUUCAUUUUAUAAAGAUAUAAUAAGACUUUUAUUGUGUUUUUUUCUUAUUCUAUAUAUGAGGGAAAUCGGAAAAGAUAAAGAAGUUCUUUCAAAGAAACUUUCUAGAUCUCUCAUUACUGCAGAUCCUUUAUAGCAGUGUCCAAGUACAGAUCCCCUGUUAGGGCAAAGCUAAAAGGAACCUGCCAAAUUAUAAUUUCUCCUGUAGUGUGUUUUAUCUCGGGGUUUCCUUUUUCAAAAAUCUAAACACUAUCCAUCUAUAAAUGACUAUCUUAAAUCAAGUUUAGAGAAUGGCCAAUAAUCUGUAUAUAGUUUAUAAAUACAUGACAAAAAAAUUUCUGCUGAGCCAGAGUGCAUCAUAACCUUCACAUCACCUCAAAAUAUUUUAUGUCUCAUUCUUUUUUAGUGAAUUGGCAUGAAUAUUUUUUAAGUCUACAGAUUUUAUGUUAGAGGAGAAUCACAAGCGUUAAUGAUAAUUAGGUUUUCUCACACCACACUAUGGCAAUAUUAGCACGUCCAAGGCUUUUAACCCACCCGAUACAUAGAAUACAUUUGGCAAUAAAAGAAUCCUUUUUAGAUGUGUUUAUGGUAACUUCAGAAACACAAAUGUGGUCUGUGGAUUAUGAGCACUUAUGCUUGUUUUGUCAAACAGUAACCUACAUGAAAGCAACUCUAUCAGUAAGAAGCUGGUUUCACAGAAAAAUGGGGAAACUACCUCAAUUCAGCUUGCUGAUUUUCUGACAUUGCUACCUCCCUGCCCAUUAUUUUUGUGUUUCUAUAUGGAAAUUUGAAGCAGGUAGCUUCUCAAGCUCUACAUAGACCAAACUGAAGAAAGAUCACUUGAAUACACAAACUGGUGCAGAAGAACAUUCAGCAUAUAAAGUUACUACCAAGCUCUUGCAUCAAGAAAAAAGAGUGAGAUUUUUGAACUCUAUACAUCAUAAAUGGCAUGCUUUCAGAGAGACUUAAGAUCCCAAAGAUUAUAACAGAGAGAAAUUUCCCCUGCAAGUAUUAUGUAACCGUAAUUAAAAAAAAUGGAUAAAGGAGCUAAUUUUACAUACAUUUCAAUAGAAAUUUGCAUAUAUCUAACAUAUUCAUUUUGUCCUGUUUACACUAGCAAGGGUUGAAUUCCUGAACUUGAAUCUUUUUCUUCAUAUACAUUUUCUUAUAGAGCUAUUGAUGAAUUAAUUAAUGAUUUUUUAAUUGUUCUUUUUUCUACCACCUUUUGUGACUCAAUUUUUUAAGAUCCUGAGACAUUUAUGACCUGCUUAUCUGUAUAUUUUUAUGUGUUCAUCUGAAUUUCCAGUAAGAAGUAAAUUUCCGUCAAACAGAUGUAGUAUACCGCUAUAAUACAGCUUAUUUAGCCAGCUAGAAGUAAAACUUAUGCCACCGAAACAAACAAAUGAUUACUUUCUUGUCAAAUAAUAUUUUUGUCACAUUUUUAGACUUGGUUGUUUUUCCUCUUUGAAAUCUAGUUCACAUGACACUUUAUCAGGGACACUAGCUAAUGGACCUCAUGUUUAGUUAAUUCUGAAACUGAUGGAUUGUUGCACAGCCUCUGCUCCUAACUGAUAAAUAUUUGCGGCAAAGUCCAAAUUUUGUGAAGGAGAAAUUGGUUGGAAUUAAAUUUUAUGGGCGUCCCUUCUUGUUUCCACUAUAUUAUAAUUAAACACACUGAAGUUGAAUAAUAAAUUACUGUGCUAAAAUAAUUGUAAUAACAAAAAUGAACUGACAGAACAAUUAUCUUGAAGUAACAAUAAUCAGGAAAAUAUCUAACAAAAAGCACGUAAGGGAAAUAUCCUUAACUUCCUGUAAAAAAAAUUCACAUUGACUCUAAAUUAAGAUGUAGUUUAUCAUCUGUAUUUUAAAAUAUCCAUCAUAACUAAAAAUGUUGACAUAUUAAGGAAAGGAUCUUUAAGAUCUAGGUUUAAGAUUCUUAUUAGUAUUAACUUAAUUGGUAUGACAAAACUUUUCAUAAUAGAUAUAAGCAUAUAAGGGAAUUAGUAACAUUUAUAAAGGACCCACAUAUUUAAUUUUAGGCAUUGUCUUCAGCUUCCCUGGACCCCCAACACAUGUUGAAAUGUUAUUGACUAGCUUGCUUUUUUUAAGGAAUGACAUUAAAAAUUUCGACUGACUUUCUACAUUACUGUAAAGAUCAAAAGGGAGAGGAAAAAUAGUUUACAAGUUUUCUAAAGAUCAACUCCAGACUAAUCUAUAUCAUCCCCUAAUAAUGAAAAAACAAUUAGUUUUUAGAAGUUGUCUAUCAGUACUGUACCGAAGUGCUACUGCUUGGAUUUUUUUGUUGUGGUUUUAAAGAGAUGGGGUCUUGCUCUGUCACAAAGACUGAAGGGCAGUGGCACAAUCCCAGCUCACUGCAGCCUCAGACUCUUGGGCUCAAGUGAUCCUGCUGUCUCAGCCUUCUGCGUAGCCAUGAUCACAGGUUUGAGCCACAGCACUUGGCCUGUGAUGUAUUGCAGAGGGAAAAAAACCAACACUACAGAAGUAUAAUGCAUGUCAAUUCAGAUUUAGAGAGUGUAAAAAACAAAAACCCAAAGUCCAACUAUUUAGUUUUGAGCAAAUCUGAAGAUAUUGGCAUGAAUAUCCUUUCUUCUCUAAGAAAAUUUUUGAGAUAACAAUAUAUAUGAAGUUCCCAGUACAUUGUAGACCAAGGUGUUAAAAUUUAAUUAGUUCAUUUUUAGUAAUUCAUAAUUUUAACUUACCACAUAAACAAUUACUAUGCAUUUCUAAGUAACGUUUUCAAUAUAGCUUAUAUUAGAUUUCUGCACAUCAUUAAAUUACGAAGAUGGCACAAAAGCAAAGCAGCAACAUUGCACAAUAGCUUAUGGAAGCAUUUUUGUGCGAAUGGAUUUUACAUAAGAAGCUUUUCUGAGCUCAUAAAAUAUAUUCAAUGGAUCCCAACAUUAAAUUUAACUUUGCAAUCAGCAAAUAUGUUCUUUAUAACAUCUUAAAAAUAUUAAACAAUUAAAUUUUCAUUUGUAGGCUAGCAGAACUUAAAUGUGUUGGUAGUUGCUUCUUUCCUGAUUAGGCCAUAAGAAGAAACUUUCCUAUUUACUAAUUAACACUGAUUACACUCUCUUUGGUUUAAAAGGGAAACUUUCACCUGUACACAUACACACUCUGAUUCCAUUUAUUUACAGCCUGCAGAAGAAGUAGCUUGUUUACGAUAUUUAAAACUUUGUGAUUUCUGCAAUAAAACAGGUAGUUAAUAUAGUUUCGCAUAAUCUCAUUGAAAGAUAUUGCUAUUCCUUCUUUAUUUAAAAAAAAAUUUAAAAGUCAGCACUUCUUUCACAUCUAGCACCUAUAAGUUACUAUUCAAAUGUCUUGAUUUCAGCUAAGUUUUGAUGUUUCUUUUUCUCUUAAUAGUAUGUCAAAAGCAUUGUUCUCAUUUGAUAAUUUGUGUCCCGUUACAGUAUUUCAAAGGUAAAUGCAAACUAAUUUUUAGGAAGGCUUGUGAAAGAACUUUGAUUUAUGUGAAGAAAUCAAGAAAGACUAUACAUGAACAAAUCUCUAUUGGGAUAAACAAGUCUCUUCAACCACAAUAUGAACAACGGAAGAGCAGAAACCAAACAAGUUAGCAAACUUAUGGUAAGGUGACAGGACCUAAACUAGAGUUACAGAGAAAAGUUUUCCAGGAAAGAAUAAUGAAGUCAUUUGUAGUGAUAAAAAUCUUAUACACUACACCAAAUGUUACAGAUGUAUUCCGAAAAGUAAAAUGGGAGUUUCCUAUAUUCUGAUUUCAUUCUGCUAAUUCCACGGGAAACAUUAAAUACUUUAAACACUCUUGAGAUAUUUCGUAUCUAGCUAUACCUUGUCUCAAGGAAACAUCAAUAUUUUAUAAAUGUUUCUUAAAUAUAAGUAUUUUGUCUGAAUUCAUCUUCACUCUCUAAUCUGCUGGCUCUAUUGAACACCAACAGAGUUAAUGCUUUUAGUAGCUUUGUACCUUUUAAAGCUCUAUUAUGAAUCUUUCUAAUACAUAUGAAAUUAAUAUUAUAUUAGAAUUAUGUACAUUAUACAAAAUAAUUCAUAACCAAGAAAUAUUCAUACUAUAGAAUAAUUUAUUAUUAUAUAUAUGAAUAUUACAUUGAGACUGAACAAAUAACCACUCUGCUCCAAAUAUUACUCUCAAGUUCUCUGCCUUUAAUUAUUAUAGUCAAUUCAUAAAAUUCUACAUACAGUUGUACAUGGUGGGUUAUCAAAGUACUCCAUAAUCCAAAUGCAUCUAAAAGUAUUCCAAAUGCGCCUUUCAUUCUAGAAUACUAAAGGAAAGCGUUUGAAAGAAGAGGAAAGUAAAGCAGACUUCUAACUAUUUAAUUUAAACAUUGCCAUUCAGAUUGAAUAAUUUUUAAAUGAUGAUGCUCCACUCUUUGAUCUACAGACAAGGUUACAAAAGAUUUACAAUUAGUCCAAAAUCAGAGGAUUUUAAAUCUUAAAGGAGUUAAGUUUGUCUCAAUGAUCCAAGACUACAAAAUUUCUUGCUACAUUGGCAAGGAAAUAUGUUUAAAGCCGAGAACUAAAAUAGCUUUUUAAAAUUUAAAAAUUCCUCUGUUUCUUCUGAAUGUAAAACAGGCAAAAUGAUCCUGACUUCAAAAUGAAAUAUAUUGAUUGCUCUCAAAAGAUGUUUGACAAAGUUAAGUCAGUAUCUUCAAUGCUUUAACAGUAGGUAGAGGUCUUUGGGGUUGGAACUCAGGAUACAGUGACUAGGACAGAGUGCAUUCUUAGGCUAAUUAGUGCCUAGUCCUCUGGAGUAUUUUUUAAUGCCCUGAAUUUCAAGUUGUCAAACUGGUUUACAUAUUGAAUGACAUUUUGAAUCAAUAAAAAUGAGAAAAAAACAUUUAAAUUUGGUUUUCAUGACUCAUUUGAGAAUAAAGAUUUCCUUCAUCACCCUAAGUAAUAAAAGCUGAUAUGUCUUGAAACAACUAUAGACAAUCAGAAUGUGUUCAUUUAUAAAGUAUCACUGGUUUGUAUAUUUUAAUGCUGACCUUUGCCUGUGAACUAGAAAAUCAAGAUUUGUAGAGUCAGGUUGAUUUGCCUUCAUUUAAUUCCUGCAAAUGCAUUGGAAGUGGAUGGAUAACUUGGAACUUUUUCCAUACUGUUUUCCCCCUCACCAAGCAUUAAAUCUAAUUCAAAAUAUGUCUUUCUAAAAAACAAUAGUUUAUUUUUAAAACUAACAACUAAUUGUGUUAUUCCUUGUUGAUAAGAAAGUCACUUUUUAGAAACAAGAAUAUAGCUAUUGUGGCUUUGGUCGCUUAGGAUUCUCAUAUAUUUACACAUGGCAUUAUUCUUUUCAUAUACACCUACCAGAUUUCAAGCUAUUGGAUAUUUCCCUUGUACAACCUUUACAUCCUUUUUUUUUCCUUAAAUGCUCUGUACAAUCACAUGUAAAGUCAUGAGCUACAAACCUCAAUAAAAAUAUCAGUAAACAAGAA